GCAGAUCGUCGCGGAGCCACGGCAGGAGGAGGCAGGGGCCGCGGGCGAGCCUGCGCUGGGCCGGCCGAGGGAAGCGCGCCGCUGGGGCCGGGGGCGGCGGGGACCCCACGGGAGCGCGCGCGGCGGGGACCCCCAGGGGCUUGCGGGCGGCCGGGGGAGGCUCGGCGGACAAAGGGGCGGAGGGCGGAGGGCCAUGGCGUCCCCGGCACCCGCCGCCGCCCGCCCCCGAGCCGCGCCGCCAGCCGUCCCGGCCCGCCCCGGAGCCCCCAAGAUGCGCCCCAGAGCCCGCGGAGCCGCCGCCCGCGGGGAGGUGACCUGGAACUCCCCUCGGUACUGACAUGAUGACAGUGUGCAGGCCGGCCAAGGGCAGCCACAGCCAGACUGAAAACCUGAGCUACAAAUUGGCUGACAAGGUCAAGGUGGAAGGUCCAAGGACUGAGAAAGACCCUCGAAGGCAUCCACUUUAGUCCUCCAUUCCAUUCCUAGAGACUGAUCAGGAGUCAGGCUUCAGAAGGAGUCCCCUGGAAGGCCUCCACAACCUCACGCUAGAGUCAAGAAUGGAUAUGUUCAGCUUGGAUAUGAUCAUCAGUGACCCAGCUGCAGAAGCCAGCAGGGCUGGGAAGAAGCAGCUCAGAGGUGUUCAGAACCCUUGCCCAUCUGCCAGAGCCAGACCCCGGCACAAGUCCCUCAACAUAAAGGACAAGAUAUCAGAAUGGGAAGGGAAGAAAGAGGUGCCCACUCCUGCACCCAGCAGGAGAGCAGACGGACAGGAGGAUUAUCUGCCGUCCUCUACGGUGGAGAGGAGGAGUAGUGAUGGGGUGAGAACUCAGGUCACAGAGGCUAAGAAUGGAAUGAGGCCAGGAACAGAGAGCACAGAGAAGGAGAGGAAUAAAGGAGCAGUGAACGUCGGGGGACAGGACCCAGAGCCGGGGCAAGACCUAAGCCAGCCAGAACGGGAAGUGGAUCCUAGCUGGGGCCGAGGCCGAGAGCCAAGACUUGGCAAGCUACGCUUUCAGAACGAUCCCCUCUCCGUGCUGAAGCAGGUCAAGAAACUCGAGCAGGCUUUGAAGGAUGGGUCGGCAGGGCUGGAUCCCCAGUUACCAGGGACUUGUUACUCCCCACACUGCCCUCCUGACAAGGCAGAGGCAGGGUCCACCCUUCCUGAGAACCUGGGAGGCGGGAGUGGCUCAGAAGUCAGCCAGAGGGUCCACCCCUCGGACCUGGAAGGCAGGGAGCCCACCCCUGAGCUUGUGGAGGACAGGAAAGGUUCAUGCAGAAGGCCCUGGGACCGGAGCCUUGAGAACGUGUAUAGGGGCUCGGAGGGUUCCCCCACAAAGCCCUUCAUCAACCCUCUGCCAAAACCCCGGAGAACGUUCAAACAUGCCGGAGAAGGGGACAAAGAUGGGAAGCCUGGCAUCGGCUUCAGGAAAGAGAAAAGAAAUCUGCCUCCUCUGCCCUCUCUACCUCCCCCGCCUCUGCCCUCCUCUCCCCCACCUUCCUCUGUGAACAGAAGACUGUGGACCGGGAGACAGAAAUCCAGUGCAGACCACAGAAAGUCCUAUGAGUUUGAAGAUUUACUGCAGUCUUCCUCUGAGAGCAGCAGGGUGGACUGGUACGCGCAGACUAAGCUGGGGCUGACACGCACUUUAUCGGAGGAGAACGUCUAUGAAGACAUUCUAGAUCCGCCAAUGAAGGAGAACCCUUAUGAGGACAUCGAGUUACAUGGUCGCUGCCUGGGAAAGAAGUGUGUCUUGAAUUUUCCUGCUUCUCCCACCUCUUCCAUCCCUGACACACUCACCAAGCAGUCAUUGUCCAAACCUGCUUUUUUCCGACAAAAUUCAGAGAGGAGGAACUUCAAGCUGCUGGACACUAGGAAGCUGAGUCGGGAUGGAACUGGGUCCCCUUCCAAAAUCAGCCCUCCCUCCACUCCCAGCAGCCCUGAUGACAUUUUCUUUAACCUUGGAGACCCACAGAACGGCAGGAAGAAGAGAAAGAUACCCAAGCUGGUGUUGCGAAUCAACGCCAUUUAUGAGGUCCGGAGAGGAAAGAAACGGGUGAAGAGGCUGUCCCAGUCAAUGGAGAGCAACUCAGGAAAAGUGACAGAUGAGAACAGUGAGUCUGACAGUGACACAGAGGAGAAGCUGAAAGCUCACAGCCAGCGCCUGGUCAACGUGAAGUCCCGGCUGAAGCAGGCGCCUCGGUACCCAUCACUUGCCCGGGAACUCAUCGAGUACCAGGAGAGGCAGCUCUUCGAGUACUUUGUGGUUGUGUCUUUGCACAAGAAGCAGGCCGGGGCUGCCUACGUGCCAGAACUCACCCAACAGUUCCCUCUGAAGUUGGAAAGGUCUUUCAAGUUCAUGAGAGAAGCUGAGGACCAACUGAAGGCCAUUCCCCAGUUCUGUUUUCCCGAUGCCAAGGAUUGGGUUCCUGUCCAGCAGUUCACCAGUGAAACAUUCUCAUUUGUCUUAACUGGAGAAGAUGGGAGCAGAAGGUUCGGUUACUGCCGAAGACUGCUGCCUGGAGGCAAAGGGAAGCGCCUUCCUGAAGUUUACUGCAUUGUGAGCCGCCUGGGAUGCUUCAGCCUCUUUUCAAGGAUCUUGGAUGAGGUGGAAAAAAGACGAGGCAUCUCUCCUGCCCUGGUUCAGCCACUCAUGAGAAGUGUCAUGGAAGCCCCUUUCCCAGCCCUGGGCAAAACCAUCCUUGUCAAGAACUUCCUGCCAGGUUCAGGAACUGAGGUGAUCGAACUGUGCCGCCCGCUGGACUCCCGGCUCGAGCACGUGGACUUUGAGUCUCUCUUCUCCUCCCUCAGCGUCCGCCACCUGGUCUGUGUGUUUGCCUCCCUGCUUCUGGAGAGGAGGGUCAUCUUCAUUGCAGACAAGCUCAGCAUCCUGUCCAAGUGCUGCCACGCGAUGGUGGCGCUGAUCUACCCCUUCGCCUGGCAGCACACCUACAUCCCGGUGCUGCCACCCGCCAUGGUCGACAUCGUGUGCUCGCCGACGCCCUUCCUCAUCGGGCUGCUCUCCAGCUCGCUGCCACUGCUCAGGGAGCUGCCGCUGGAAGAGGUCCUUGUGGUUGACCUCGUCAACAGCCGGUUCCUCAGACAGAUGGACGAUGAGGACUCCAUCCUGCCCCGGAAGCUUCAGGUGGCCCUGGAACACAUUCUGGAACAGAGGAACGAGCUGGCUUGUGAGCAGGACGAAGGGCCCCUAGACGGCAGGCACGGUCCAGAGUCCAGCCCCUUGAACGAGGUGGUGUCUGAAGCCUUUGUCCGCUUCUUCGUGGAGAUUGUGGGACACUACUCUUUGUUCCUGACGUCGGGCGAGCGUGAGGAGAGAACCCUGCAGCGGGAGGCCUUCCGCAAAGCUGUCUCCUCCAAGAGCCUCCGCCACUUCCUGGAGGUCUUCAUGGAGACUCAGAUGUUUCGGGGCUUCAUCCAGGAGCGGGAGCUGCGCCGGCAGGAUGCCAAAGGUCUGUUUGAGGUCCGAGCCCAAGAGUAUCUGGAAACACUCCCCAGUGGAGAGCACAGCGGUGUCAAUAAGUUCCUGAAGGGACUAGGCAAUAAAAUGAAAUUUCUCCACAAGAAAUAACUCUCAGCCUCAAGGGAAAACUUCCUCCUAGUGCAGCCCUAUGCUUUAAAAACAGUUCCUGGUGGCCUUUCUGAAAGGCUGGGUCCCAGGUUGUCACGGUGCGGAACUGGAGGCCGCGGUGGCUUCUGGCCGAGGCUGGGCUCUUCCCUGGAUGAGGACCUGGGAGCCGCCUGGGAGGACAGCCCCAGAAAGGGAGCCCGAGACCAGGCGUGUCGCCGACAUGCAAAUGGGUUGUUUUGGUGGUUGGGUUUUUUUUUUUAUCUUAGAUAUUAAAAGUAAGAAAAAUG